AUUGCAGCUGGGACAGCCCGGAGUGUGGUUAGCAGCUCGGCAAGCGCUGCCCAGGUCCUGGGGUGGUGGCAGCCAGCGGGAGCAGGAAAGGAAGCAUGUUCCCAGGCUGCCCACGCCUCUGGGUCCUGGUGGUCUUGGGCACCAGCUGGGUAGGCUGGGGGAGCCAAGGGACAGAAGCGGCACAGCUAAGGCAGUUCUACGUGGCUGCUCAGGGCAUCAGUUGGAGCUACCGACCUGAGCCCACAAACUCAAGUUUGAAUCUUUCUGUAACUUCCUUUAAGAAAAUUGUCUACAGAGAGUAUGAACCAUAUUUUAAGAAAGAAAAACCACAAUCUACCAUUUCAGGACUUCUUGGGCCUACUUUAUAUGCUGAAGUCGGAGACAUCAUAAAAGUUCACUUUAAAAAUAAGGCAGAUAAGCCCUUGAGCAUCCAUCCUCAAGGAAUUAGGUACAGUAAAUUAUCAGAAGGUGCUUCUUACCUUGACCACACAUUCCCUGCGGAGAAGAUGGACGACGCUGUGGCUCCAGGCCGAGAAUACACCUAUGAAUGGAGUAUCAGUGAGGACAGUGGACCCACCCAUGAUGACCCUCCAUGCCUCACACACAUCUAUUACUCCCAUGAAAAUCUGAUCGAGGAUUUCAACUCGGGGCUGAUUGGGCCCCUGCUUAUCUGUAAAAAAGGGACCCUAACUGAGGGUGGGACACAGAAGACGUUUGACAAGCAAAUCGUGCUACUAUUUGCUGUGUUUGAUGAAAGCAAGAGCUGGAGCCAGUCAUCAUCCCUAAUGUACACAGUCAAUGGAUAUGUGAAUGGGACAAUGCCAGAUAUAACAGUUUGUGCCCAUGACCACAUCAGCUGGCAUCUGCUGGGAAUGAGCUCGGGGCCAGAAUUAUUCUCCAUUCAUUUCAACGGCCAGGUCCUGGAGCAGAACCAUCAUAAGGUCUCAGCCAUCACCCUUGUCAGUGCUACAUCCACUACCGCAAAUAUGACUGUGGGCCCAGAGGGAAAGUGGAUCAUAUCUUCUCUCACCCCAAAACAUUUGCAAGCUGGGAUGCAGGCUUACAUUGACAUUAAAAACUGCCCAAAGAAAACCAGGAAUCUUAAGAAAAUAACUCGUGAGCAGAGGCGGCACAUGAAGAGGUGGGAAUACUUCAUUGCUGCAGAGGAAGUCAUUUGGGACUAUGCACCUGUAAUACCAGCGAAUAUGGACAAAAAAUACAGGUCUCAGCAUUUGGAUAAUUUCUCAAACCAAAUUGGAAAACAUUAUAAGAAAGUUAUGUACACACAGUACGAAGAUGAGUCCUUCACCAAACAUACAGUGAAUCCCAAUAUGAAAGAAGAUGGGAUUUUGGGUCCUAUUAUCAGAGCCCAGGUCAGAGACACACUCAAAAUCGUGUUCAAAAAUAUGGCCAGCCGCCCCUAUAGCAUUUACCCUCAUGGAGUGACCUUCUCGCCUUAUGAAGAUGAAGUCAACUCUUCUUUCACCUCAGGCAGGAACAACACCAUGAUCAGAGCAGUUCAACCAGGGGAAACCUAUACUUAUAAGUGGAACAUCUUAGAGUUUGAUGAACCCACAGAAAAUGAUGCCCAGUGCUUAACAAGACCAUACUACAGUGACGUGGACAUCAUGAGAGACAUCGCCUCUGGGCUAAUAGGACUACUUCUAAUCUGUAAGAGCAGAUCCCUGGACAGGCGAGGAAUACAGAGGGCAGCAGACAUCGAACAGCAGGCUGUGUUUGCUGUGUUUGAUGAGAACAAAAGCUGGUACCUUGAGGACAACAUCAACAAGUUUUGUGAAAAUCCUGAUGAGGUGAAACGUGAUGACCCCAAGUUUUAUGAAUCAAACAUCAUGAGCACUAUCAAUGGCUAUGUGCCUGAGAGCAUAACUACUCUUGGAUUCUGCUUUGAUGACACUGUCCAGUGGCACUUCUGUAGUGUGGGGACCCAGAAUGAAAUUUUGACCAUCCACUUCACUGGGCACUCAUUCAUCUAUGGAAAGAGGCAUGAGGACACCUUGACCCUCUUCCCCAUGCGUGGAGAAUCUGUGACGGUCACAAUGGAUAAUGUUGGAACUUGGAUGUUAACUUCCAUGAAUUCUAGUCCAAGAAGCAAAAAGCUGAGGCUGAAAUUCAGGGAUGUUAAAUGUAUCCCAGAUGAUGAUGAAGACUCAUAUGAGAUUUUUGAACCUCCAGAAUCUACAGUCAUGGCUACACGGAAAAUGCAUGAUCGUUUAGAACCUGAAGAUGAAGAGAGUGAUGCUGACUAUGAUUACCAGAACAGACUGGCUGCAGCAUUAGGAAUCAGGUCAUUCCGAAACUCAUCAUUGAAUCAGGAAGAAGAAGAGUUCAAUCUUACUGCCCUAGCUCUGGAGAAUGGCACUGAAUUCGUUUCUUCAAACACAGAUAUAAUUGUUGGUUCAAAUUAUUCUUCCCCAAGUAAUAUUAGUAAGUUCACUGUCAAUAACCUUGCAGAACCUCAGAAAGCCCCUUCUCACCAACAAGCCACCACAGCUGGUUCCCCACUGAGACACCUCAUUGGCAAGAACUCAGUUCUCAAUUCUUCCACAGCAGAGCAUUCCAGCCCAUAUUCUGAAGACCCUAUAGAGGAUCCUCUACAGCCAGAUGUCACAGGGAUACGUCUACUUUCACUUGGUGCUGGAGAAUUCAAAAGUCAAGAACAUGCUAAGCAUAAGGGACCCAAGGUAGAAAGAGAUCAAGCAGCAAAGCACAGGUUCUCCUGGAUGAAAUUACUAGCACAUAAAGUUGGGAGACACCUAAGCCAAGACACUGGUUCUCCUUCCGGAAUGAGGCCCUGGGAGGACCUUCCUAGCCAAGACACUGGUUCUCCUUCCAGAAUGAGGCCCUGGAAGGACCCUCCUAGUGAUCUGUUACUCUUAAAACAAAGUAACUCAUCUAAGAUUUUGGUUGGGAGAUGGCAUUUGGCUUCUGAGAAAGGUAGCUAUGAAAUAAUCCAAGAUACUGAUGAAGACACAGCUGUUAACAAUUGGCUGAUCAGCCCCCAGAAUGCCUCACGUGCUUGGGGAGAAAGCACCCCUCUUGCCAACAAGCCUGGAAAGCAGAGUGGCCACCCAAAGUUUCCUAGAGUUAGACAUAAAUCUCUACAAGUAAGACAGGAUGGAGGAAAGAGUAGACUGAAGAAAAGCCAGUUUCUCAUUAAGACACGAAAAAAGAAAAAAGAGAAGCACACACACCAUGCUCCUUUAUCUCCGAGGACCUUUCACCCUCUAAGAAGUGAAGCCUACAACACAUUUUCAGAAAGAAGACUUAAGCAUUCGUUGGUGCUUCAUAAAUCCAAUGAAACAUCUCUUCCCACAGACCUCAAUCAGACAUUGCCCUCUAUGGAUUUUGGCUGGAUAGCCUCACUUCCUGACCAUAAUCAGAAUUCCUCAAAUGACACUGGUCAGGCAAGCUGUCCUCCAGGUCUUUAUCAGACAGUGCCCCCAGAGGAACACUAUCAAACAUUCCCCAUUCAAGACCCUGAUCAAAUGCACUCUACUUCAGACCCCAGUCACAGAUCCUCUUCUCCAGAGCUCAGUGAAAUGCUUGAGUAUGACCGAAGUCACAAGUCCUUCCCCACAGAUAUAAGUCAAAUGUCCCCUUCCUCAGAACAUGAAGUCUGGCAGACAGUCAUCUCUCCAGACCUCAGCCAGGUGACCCUCUCUCCAGAACUCAGCCAGACAAACCUCUCUCCAGACCUCAGCCACACGACUCUCUCUCCAGAACUCAUUCAGAGAAACCUUUCCCCAGCCCUCGGUCAGAUGCCCAUUUCUCCAGACCUCAGCCAUACAACCCUUUCUCCAGACCUCAGCCAUACAACCCUUUCUUUAGACCUCAGCCAGACAAACCUCUCUCCAGAACUCAGUCAGACAAACCUUUCUCCAGCCCUCGGUCAGAUGCCCCUUUCUCCAGACCUCAGCCAUACAACCCUUUCUCUAGACUUCAGCCAGACAAACCUCUCUCCAGAACUCAGCCAUAUGACUCUCUCUCCAGAACUCAGUCAGACAAACCUUUCCCCAGCCCUCGGUCAGAUGCCCAUUUCUCCAGACCUCAGCCAUACAACCCUUUCUCUAGACUUCAGCCAGACAAACCUCUCUCCAGAACUCAGUCAAACAAACCUUUCCCCAGCCCUCGGUCAGAUGCCCCUUUCUCCAGACCCCAGCCAUACAACCCUUUCUCUAGACCUCAGCCAGACAAACCUCUCUCCAGAACUCAGUCAGACAAACCUUUCCCCAGACCUCAGUGAGAUGCCCCUCUUUGCAGAUCUCAGUCAAAUUCCCCUUACCCCAGACCUCGACCAGAUGACACUUUCUCCAGACCUUGGUGAGACAGAUCUUUCCCCAAACUUUGGUCAGAUGUCCCUUUCCCCAGACCUCAGCCAGGUGACUCUCUCUCCAGACAUCAGUGACACCACCCUUCUCCCGGAUCUCAGCCAGAUAUCACCUCCUCCAGACCUUGAUCAGAUAUUCUACCCUUCUGAAUCUAGUCAGUCAUUGCUUCUUCAAGAAUUUAAUGAGUCUUUUCCUUAUCCAGACCUUGGUCAGAUGCCAUCUCCUUCAUCUCCUACUCUCAAUGAUACUUUUCUAUCAAAGGAAUUUAAUCCACUGGUUAUAGUGGGCCUCAGUAAAGAUGGUACAGAUUACAUUGAGAUCAUUCCAAAGGAAGAGGUCCAGAGCAGUGAAGAUGACUAUGCUGAAAUUGAUUAUGUGCCCUAUGAUGACCCCUACAAAACUGAUGUUAGGACAAACAUCAACUCCUCCAGAGAUCCUGACAACAUUGCAGCAUGGUACCUCCGCAGCAACAAUGGAAACAGAAGAAAUUAUUACAUUGCUGCUGAAGAAAUAUCCUGGGAUUAUUCAGAAUUUGUACAAAGGGAAACAGAUAUUGAAGACUCUGAUGAUAUUCCAGAAGAUACCACAUAUAAGAAAGUAGUUUUUCGAAAGUACCUCGACAGCACUUUUACCAAACGUGAUCCUCGAGGGGAGUAUGAAGAGCAUCUCGGAAUUCUUGGUCCUAUUAUCAGAGCUGAAGUGGAUGAUGUUAUCCAAGUUCGUUUUAAAAAUUUAGCAUCCAGACCGUAUUCUCUACAUGCCCAUGGACUUUCCUAUGAAAAAUCAUCAGAGGGAAAGACUUAUGAAGAUGACUCUCCUGAAUGGUUUAAGGAAGAUAAUGCUGUUCAGCCAAAUAGCAGUUAUACCUACGUAUGGCAUGCCACUGAGCGAUCAGGGCCAGAAAGUCCUGGCUCUGCCUGUCGGGCUUGGGCCUACUACUCAGCUGUGAACCCAGAAAAAGAUAUUCACUCAGGCUUGAUAGGUCCCCUCCUAAUCUGCCAAAAAGGAAUACUACAUAAGGACAGCAACAUGCCUAUGGACAUGAGAGAAUUUGUCUUACUAUUUAUGACCUUUGAUGAAAAGAAGAGCUGGUACUAUGAAAAGAAGUCCCGAAGUUCUUGGAGACUCACAUCCUCAGAAAUGAAAAAAUCCCAUGAGUUUCACGCCAUUAAUGGGAUGAUCUACAGCUUGCCUGGCCUGAAAAUGUAUGAGCAAGAGUGGGUGAGGUUACACCUGCUGAACAUAGGCGGCUCCCAAGACAUUCACGUGGUUCACUUUCACGGCCAGACCUUGCUGGAAAAUGGCAAUAAACAGCACCAGUUAGGGGUCUGGCCCCUUCUGCCUGGUUCAUUUAAAACUCUUGAAAUGAAGGCAUCAAAACCUGGCUGGUGGCUCCUAAACACAGAGGUUGGAGAAAACCAGAGAGCAGGGAUGCAAACGCCAUUUCUUAUCAUGGACAGAGACUGUAGGAUGCCAAUGGGACUAAGCACUGGUAUCAUAUCUGAUUCACAGAUCAAGGCUUCAGAGUUUCUGGGUUACUGGGAGCCCAGAUUAGCAAGAUUAAACAAUGGUGGAUCUUAUAAUGCUUGGAGUGUAGAAAAACUUGCAGCAGAAUUUGCCUCUAAACCUUGGAUCCAGGUGGACAUGCAAAAGGAAGUCAUAAUCACAGGGAUCCAGACCCAAGGUGCCAAACACUACCUGAAGUCCUGCUAUACCACAGAGUUCUAUGUAGCUUACAGUUCCAACCAGAUCAACUGGCAGAUCUUCAAAGGGAACAGCACAAGGAAUGUGAUGUAUUUUAAUGGCAAUUCAGAUGCCUCUACAAUAAAAGAGAAUCAGUUUGACCCACCUAUUGUGGCUAGAUAUAUUAGGAUCUCUCCAACUCGAGCCUAUAACAGACCUACCCUUCGAUUGGAACUGCAAGGUUGUGAGGUAAAUGGAUGUUCCACACCCCUGGGUAUGGAAAAUGGAAAGAUAGAAAACAAGCAAAUCACAGCUUCUUCGUUUAAGAAAUCUUGGUGGGGAGAUUACUGGGAACCCUUCCGUGCCCGUCUGAAUGCCCAGGGACGUGUGAAUGCCUGGCAAGCCAAGGCAAACAACAAUAAGCAGUGGCUAGAAAUUGAUCUACUCAAGAUCAAGAAGAUAACGGCAAUUAUAACACAGGGCUGCAAGUCUCUGUCCUCUGAAAUGUAUGUAAAGAGCUAUACCAUCCACUACAGUGAGCAGGGAGUGGAAUGGAAACCAUACAGGCUGAAAUCCUCCAUGGUGGACAAGAUUUUUGAAGGAAAUACUAAUACCAAAGGACAUGUGAAGAACUUUUUCAACCCCCCAAUCAUUUCCAGGUUUAUCCGUGUCAUUCCUAAAACAUGGAAUCAAAGUAUUGCACUUCGCCUGGAACUCUUUGGCUGUGAUAUUUACUAGAAUUGAACAUUCAAAAACCCCUGGAAGAGACUCUUUAAGACCUCAAACCAUUUAGAAUGGGCAAUGUAUUUUACGCUGUGUUAAAUGUUAACAGUUUUCCACUAUUUCUCUUUCUUUUCUAUUAGUGAAUAAAAUUUUAUACAAGAAGCUUUUAUAAUGUAACUCCUUGCUACCAGUAAGUAAGAUAAUGGCUAUUACUUCUGCAUUAAUUUGAAUACAGGUAGGAAAAUAUCAAGAACCAACAAGAAAAGGGCUUAUCUUUCUUAAUGAUUGAAAAUGCUAUGAAGUAAUAUUUAUGUAGUUAAAAUGCUUCAUUAUAACUCUUUUAAAUCCUUUACACACUAGUAAAACAGAUAUUACUUUAAAUAAUAAUUGAUAGACCUGGAUAACUUUCACAAACACAUGAUUUUUUAAUGGUUUUUCUUGAGUGAAGAGAAAAACAAUAUUAUCAAAUGAAAUAAGUACUUAAAAUAUCCUGUCUUUCCCAUAUAACAAUGAUUUUUCUGACUUUCCAUGAGUAAAAAAACAGCCAAGCAUCUUUCCAGUAGCCCCAUUGAAAUUGUGAAUCCGUCCUGGUCUCCCUAAGGACUGCACACAUUGAUAUUCAAGGUUGGUGGUCAUUAGAUAUGGAACAGAACUGAAAUAACCAUGGUAGAACUGAAUGUGUAAUGUUGGCUUUAUUCUAGCUGGUACUACAUGGCACACAGUUUCAAAACAUAAUUUCACCUACUGGAAAGCUCAGACCUGUAAAACAGAGCAUGGGAACUGCUGGUCUAAAUGCAGUUGUUCCUGCUCAAAGAGACCUCUGGCCAAACUGGCAAGCAGUUAAAGUUUUCUUUCAGGGCCUUCCUCUCUAUGGCCUCAACUUCCUCCUCUCUCUUCUUCCAGCAACUUCCCCUUUCAUCAUUCCUUUCCCUGGGGACUUGGCAUUCAGUGAUCCUGUAGAUAUUGCACAACUGGGGAACCUUUAGACAUCCUUAAAAUCACAUGAGAUAGACAGUCAUUUGGGGUGUCUGAAAUAAACCACCCCAAAACUUAGUGUUAAAAGAGCAACCAAAAAAAAUUUAUGUGAGAUUAUGGAUUUGUUACUUAGCUUGAUUUAAUCAUCCUGUAACGUGUACAUAUAUCAAAAUGUUAUGUAUACCAUAAAUAUAUAAAAUUUUAUCAACGAAAUUCAUAACAAUCUCUCAGACCACAGAGAAAUCAAAUUAGAACUGAGGACUAAGAAACUCACUCGAAACCACACAACUACAUGGAAACUGAACAACCUGCUCCUGAAUGACUACUGGGUAAAUAAUGAAAUUAAGGCAGAAAUAAAUAAGUUCCUUAAAACCAAUGAGAACAAAGAGACAACAUACCAGAAUCUCUAGGAGACAGGGCUUUGCUUUUGCUGCAUUCUAUUCGUUGUGAACACAAAUUACAGGCCAGUCUCGAUUCAGUGUAGAAGGGAACUGCAUAAGGACCACAUACCAGGAGGCAUAAUUCACUGGGAGCAUCUUUAGAAACUACCAGAGUUACCUGUUGCCCAUACCAGUGGGGUAAGCCCUAUGAAUGUAUAUGAGAGUUUCAAACAUCCACAAAACAUUGGCUUUCUAAUAUUCGUAUUCCCACUAUUCCUUUCUUUUCAUGAUUCAUGUCAUUGUCCCAUCAACAUUUCUAAGAUUUCCAUUCCGUUAAGAGCAAAAGAGAAUGUUGGAAGGUGGGGGAAAACAUUUCUUUGUUUUCUACAGGGCCAGCUUCUUGGAUGUGUGUGAUCUGUUCAGUUGCAAAGGGUCACAUGCUCAGAAGGACCGCAUGCUAAAUUUAAUGCUUUGCAGUUACCCUCUUGAAAUCCUUUAUUUUUUAAGAAGGAAUUCGACAUUUCCAUUUUUCAAUGAGCCCCACAAAUUACGCAGCUAGUCCUGGGCUUCUCUACUCUGAAAUUGGGCAGGAUCUCUCUUGAUCUAGAAUUUACUAAGGCAUAAUAGGGGCAAGAAAAUCUUAUGAAAUAAUGGGGGGUAGGGAAGAGAUGGGAAUGGAGCAUGAGAUCCAGCUUCGUUAUUCUCUACUUGAGAAAAAUAAGGCCCCAAAGAUUAAACAACUUGCCCAAGGAUAUUGCUUGUUAGUGUCAGAACUGAAACCAGAAACCAAAUGAUCAUAUCCCUAGACUUUUAGUCUGCUUUCUCUUCCAUAAAAUGAAACUUAUAAUGUUUCUAAUCCAUUGCUCAGACAGGUAGACAUGAAUAUUAAUUGAUAAUGACUAUUAAUUGAUCUGGAAAAUACUUGUUUGGGGAUCAAUAAUAUGUUUGGGCUAUUAUCUAAUGCUGUGUAGAAAUAUUAAAACCCCUGUUAUUUUGAAAUAAAAAAGAUACCCACUUUUUAU